GCAGUCGUUUCCUGUCGCUGCUUGGUAACAAUGGGGAAGAUAAUGGCUGCCUGAGCAACGUCUCCGAGCAGGCGCUGGGCUAGAGGCGGGUCUCAACCAGCUACUCAUUGGAGGCGGGCUUGAGAGCGGCGGCCAGGGAGGUGCGGAGCAGCCUCGGCGGCGGCGGCCGAACCAACCGAGUCGGAUCCUGACCCUAAAACCUAAGCAGAGUGAAGAAAACUAAAAUCCAGUUUAUUGUAUUUCAAUACUAUGUCAUAACAGUCAGGUAUUUUCCACUUGUUCAUCAAUAUGGAAAACUCAGAUUCCAAUGACAAAGGAAGUGGUGAUCAGUCUGCAGCACAGCGCAGAAGUCAGAUGGACCGAUUGGAUCGAGAAGAAGCUUUCUAUCAAUUUGUAAAUAACCUGAGUGAAGAAGAUUAUAGGCUUAUGAGAGAUAACAAUUUGCUAGGCACCCCAGGUGAAAGUACUGAGGAAGAGUUGCUGAGACGACUACAGCAAAUUAAAGAAGGCCCACCACCGCAAAACUCAGAUGAAAAUAGAGGAGGAGACUCUUCAGAUGAUGUGUCUAAUGGUGACUCUAUAAUAGACUGGCUUAACUCUGUCAGACAAACUGGAAAUACAACAAGAAGUGGGCAAAGAGGAAACCAAUCUUGGAGAGCAGUGAGUCGGACUAAUCCAAACAGUGGUGAUUUCAGAUUCAGUUUAGAGAUAAAUGUUAACCGUAAUAAUGGGAGCCAAAAUUCAGAGAAUGAAAAUGAGCCAUCUGCAAGACGUUCUAGUGGAGAAAAUGUGGAAAACAACAGCCAAAGGCAAGUGGAAAACCCACGAUCUGAAUCAACAUCUGCAAGGCCAUCUAGAUCAGAACGAAAUUCAACUGAAGCGUUAACAGAGGUCCCACCUACCAGAGGUCAGAGGAGGGCAAGAAGCAGGAGCCCAGACCAUCGGAGAACCAGAGCAAGAGCUGAAAGAAGUAGGUCACCUCUGCAUCCAAUGAGUGAAAUUCCACGAAGAUCUCAUCAUAGUAUCUCAUCUCAGACUUUUGAACAUCCUUUGGUAAAUGAGACGGAGGGAAGUUCUAGAACCCGGCACCAUGUGACAUUGAGGCAGCAAAUAUCUGGGCCUGAGUUGCUAAGUAGAGGUCUUUUUGCAGCUUCUGGAACAAGAAAUGCUUCUCAAGGAGCAGGUUCUUCAGACACAGCUGCCAGUGGUGAAUCUACAGGAUCAGGACAGAGACCUCCAACCAUAGUCCUUGAUCUUCAAGUAAGAAGAGUUCGUCCUGGAGAAUAUCGGCAGAGAGAUAGCAUAGCCAGCAGAACUCGGUCUAGGUCUCAGACACCAAACAACACUGUCACCUAUGAAAGUGAACGAGGAGGUUUUAGGCGUACAUUUUCACGUUCUGAGCGGGCAGGUGUGAGAACCUAUGUCAGUACCAUCAGAAUUCCCAUUCGUAGAAUCUUAAAUACUGGUUUAAGUGAGACUACAUCUGUUGCAAUUCAGACCAUGUUAAGGCAGAUAAUGACAGGUUUUGGUGAGUUAAGCUAUUUUAUGUACAGUGAUAGCGACUCAGAGCCUACUGGCUCAGUCUCAAAUCGAAAUAUGGAAAGGGCAGAGUCACGGAGUGGAAGAGGAGGUUCUGGUGGUGGUAGUAGUUCUGGUUCCAGUUCGAGUUCCAGUUCCAGUUCGAGUUCCAGUUCCAGUUCAAGUUCCAGUUCCAGUCCUAGUUCCAGUUCCGGUGGUGAAAGUUCAGAAACUAGCUCAGAUUUAUUUGAAGGCAGUAAUGAAGGAAGCUCAUCAUCAGGCUCAUCAGGUGCCAGGCGAGAGGGUCGACAUAGGGCCCCAGUCACAUUUGAUGAAAGUGGCUCUUUGCCCUUCCUUAGCCUGGCUCAGUUUUUCCUCUUAAAUGAGGAUGAUGAUGACCAACCUAGAGGACUCACCAAAGAACAGAUUGACAACUUGGCAAUGAGAAGUUUUGGUGAAAAUGAUGCAUUAAAAACCUGUAGUGUUUGCAUUACAGAAUAUACAGAAGGCAACAAACUUCGUAAACUACCUUGUUCCCAUGAGUACCAUGUCCACUGCAUCGAUCGCUGGUUAUCUGAGAAUUCUACCUGUCCUAUUUGUCGCAGAGCAGUCUUAGCUUCUGGUAACAGAGAAAGUGUUGUGUAAUUAAGAUCUGAACUCUCAGCUAUGUAGCUGAUAUAGUGAUGGGCAAACAGGAAUCACUUGCUUUUAUGUCCACUUUUUGAGUGGUACUUAAAUGUAAAGUAACAACCUGAAUUGAGUCAUUGCUUUCUGAAGGAAUCAUUGUCCUUUCUCCAGUUUUUGUUCCAGAAUAAAAGGAAAUAUUUUAAAAGCCACGUUAUAGGACCUAAAAAUCUGAUUUCCGUACCAGUUAAAUUGGUAGCAUCACUGUUACUGAUAAUUUAUCAUAUACACUUGUCAAUUUUUCCUUUGUUAUCUUAAAAGAUCUGCCUUAGCAAUGGCUCCUUUUUCAUGUUGAUCUUUAAAUUUUCCCACACCAUAAGAGAGGAGCAAAGGAAAUUACCAGUUUAGACUAAGUUACAGUAUGUGUUUCAUAAGUGAUUAAAGCUAUAUCAUUCCCAGUUAUUAGUUAACACAAAUUCAGCCACAUUCUGAGUAUUGUUUGUUCACCUUUCAGACUUGGUGAUACUGGACAUGUCAGUGUAAAUAACACUAAGGUUAGGAUCUUCUAAGUGUAUAACUGUCUCCUAAGCCCAUCACUGUGGCACACUGUAGAGUGAGCUUAUAGUUUAAUUGAGAUAUUUAUCUUGUGGAAAUAUUAAAAAGCCUAUGCUUGUGUAAGUGAAAAAAAAUCACAUUCAUUUGUUUAAAAAUGUAAAGCUAUUUUGUAGAGGCUCAGUACUUUUCCAAUGCACUGUUGUAUGAAUGCAUUAAAAAUUGUAAAGUACCAUGCUUAGAACUGAGAAAACUGCUUUUUGUGAGCCAACAUAGUAACAAACACACCAAACAAAGUACAAAGCUGCUUUUGUAAGUGUGUAGAUGUCAAGAGCAGAACAUAUCUAUAAUAUUUAAUGUGUGAACAGCUACUGUGACAUGCAAAGGAAAGGACAGUGCAGAAUUAAACCGUGUUGAAGACCAGUGGAAAUUGUAUAAUUUAACUUGGAUUUAGGCAGGAAGUGAAAUAUGGGAGGAGUAAAGAAAACUGAAGAAUUUAAAGUUUUCCUGAAGACAGUAAUAAUGCAGACACAAACUGGUUUCAUAUGGUGAGAGCAGCCACAGCAGCAGCUUGACCUGGUAUUCUACCUGAGUAGAUGAAGCAGAAGAUCAGCAAGUUUGGCAGAGUUUUGGUUUAAGAAAAACAAACCACUACUACCUAGCACAAGUUAAAUUUACAAGUCUGCUCCUCAAAAAUGAAAAAAUGGAGGAAAGAGACUAUAAAACCACUUUUAGCAUAUGAAUUGCAGUUGGUACACAUGUGUGUGUUAAUAGGAAAGUCUCGAAUUUGUGUUGUUUUUGAGAUUUGUCAUUUAAGGUACCAGUGCACACUUGAUCAUAUUUCAUUACUAUCUCUAACACAGUCCUAACAUCUCAAAUUUAAAGACCAGUUGAAGAUUAAGGGAUUUUUAUCCUUUGUUGAAAGUCAUGUUGGGUUAUUUGAAAUUCAAAUUUUAAUUGUGCUGCCCAUAUAUGAAAAUGAGACUGCUGACUCGCUAUCUAUGGACAUGCACUUUAUGUUGGUUUCUUAGUAGUAAGAGUAACUUCAUGAUAACCCCAGUCUUCUUGCCUAAUUUCUUUUUUGAGACUAGCUGGGGUUAGGAUUAGAAUGACUAUGGAGCAGAUAUUUGUUCUUCUGGGAAAAGCUUUAACAGGCCAAAAUAGGGAUUGAACUUGUCCUUGGCCUUUAUCAAAGCAAGCUAGCUACCCAGACGUAGUCAAAUACUCUACAAAAUAAACAAGUCUGCUUUAGGAAUUGUCUGGGUACCUUCACUGUUACCAACUUAGCUGUAAAGAUUAUUUCAAAGCUCACUCUUCCAUGAUUUCUUCUGGCUUUCAAUCCUAUCUAAGUAUCAAGGAAAUUAACUUGUAAAUAUGGUAGUUGUUUACUAAGGAUAUGUACUGCUCUUGCAAGGAAAUAAUGUCCAAACAAAGCUUCACUUAUUUUUUUUAAUAUAAGCAGAUUUCACUGUUUAUGGCGCUUAUGUAAUACAUUUUAUCUUUUUAAAAAUUUGUCCGUGUAAAAGUCAGGAUUCCUUUAUAUUUGUGAGCCUCCUUUUCUCCUUUCCUAAGGAUGUAAUCUACAGUUUUCAGAUCUGCAGGGUAGUCUUGAUUGGCUAAAAACAAAUCAAUUUUCUUCUUGGCAUAAAGUGUUUCAUUAUUAUAGGGGUGUUCAUUUUAAAUAGUUUAAAAACAAUUGCAGCACAUUCUAAGCAUAAGAGAAAGUUAUUGACAACAGGUACCUUCCUAAUCUCCCAAGACGUACUUACUCAUUUGUGAAGUAUUAAAGUAAGAGGUAACUCAAGCAGAAUGCUGGCUAUGAAUGUAGAUAUUGAAGCUAUUCAUAAACACUGGAAAUAGAAUUUUAAGCUUUUAGCCUUCAGUGGAAUGCACAUAUUGGACAUGUGCAUGUGAACACCUUUUUCAGUAGCACUCACGGAUUUCCAUUCGAUUGUAUAGAAUGAAUACAAGUGUUUUAGUGGAAUUUGCUACUUAAUUUUUAAUCUUGCGAUGUCCGUGAUUAUUACAUGCUUACUAGUGUUGUGGACAUUGAAGACAAGGUCAUUCGUAGGUGUCAGAUUACAAUGGAGAACAAAAAUCGUUUUCCCCCCACCCACAUCCAAACACCAUUCUCGAGGGAGCAUUUCUUGCAAAACACCUUACAUUUCAUUUUCUAUCUUUGCACUUUUUCUUAAGUACAGAAAAGUUGUCUUUAAGACCUAGUUUGAACUUCAUGCAGUAAGAGGAACAAGGAUAAACAAUGUUGGGAGUUCACAUUGUUCAGAGCAUAAGGAAAAGUACCAAAACCCAAAUUUUCUUGAAUAUUUCAGAUGUUUUUAAAAACUCACUUCUAGUCUGAAACAUUUGAAUUGUUUUAACUCUGAGCAGCUGACAAAGUUGAGGUUUUUUUGUUUUGUUUUGUUUUGUUUUGUUUUUUUGAGACAGAGUCUUACUUGGUUGCCCAGGAUGAAGUGCAAUGGAGCGAUCUCGGCUCACUGCAACCUCUGCCUCCUGGGUUCAAGCAAUUCUCCUGUCUCAGCCUCUCGAGUAGCUGGGAUUACAGGCGCAUGCCACCACACCUGGCUAGUUUUUAUAUUUUUAGUAGAGAUGGGGACUUCACCGUGUUGGCCAGGCUGGUCUUGAACUCCUGACCUCAAGUGAUGUGCCUGCCUCGGCCUCCGAAAAUGCUGGGAUUACAGGCGUGAGCCACCAUGUCCAGCCAAAGUUGAGGUUUAUUAGUACUAUUAGAAACAAAAUUGAGCAAGUUAAGUUAAAAGUUUGCUGACUUUGUAUCAACACUAUAGAAGAUGAGCCACCUUGUUAAUUUGGAAUAUUUGCUCUGAAAAGAACAUGUUAGUUACACCUUAAUGGUGUUAAUGGAGGUGGGGAUUGAGAAAAGUGUUCACAUUAGUGUUGGAAUGUAGGUAAUUGUACAGUUUAUAAGACCUUUAGCACCAGGAAAUAAAAUAUGUGUGUGUACACACACAGUUUUUAAAAACGAUUGGAAUUCAUCCAAACCUUAAGAUUAGGAAACUGAUUGGCUGUAAGUGUUGCCUCAAGUAAUGUGUCCCCCGCCCCAUAACAUGUCUUUUCUGUGCCAAGUAUCCUCUCCUAGUGUCAGUGUCUCAAAUUAUAUUUAUGAAGGGUUAUCACAUAAUAUGCUUUGUAUUUAACUACCUGCUUCCCAGGCGUCCAUGACAUGAAAUGGGUGAAGCAUCAGCCAUGACUUUCGGUCAGUUCCCAAAAUACCCAAAUGAUAGGGAGGUAAAGAUUGCAAAAUUCCUCUUAAAAGGCCAUUUUUACAGCUUGCUAAAAUACAGUGGCACCUUAUGGUUGUUAAUAUUUUUUCUUUUAAAGAUGGAGAAUGUUUUUAUUCUUCCCCUUUUCUCCUUUGUUCUUUUGCGAACAAAAAAAAUUAUAAUCUGCCUUAUUUGAUUUUUUUUUUAAGUUUUACCUUACAGGCUUCCCUGUCACAUGUUUUACCAUAUUAAGUACAUAGAAGCCAUGUUUGCAGGGCACUUUUAUUCUCCUAGUCUUAUAAGACUAUGCUAAUUGUUACUUUCUGAAGUAUUCUGUACCUUAGUAUGCAAGAUUGUUAAGGCACAUGUUAAAGUGUCAGGUGUGUUUUUUUCCCUUUAAUUCUUCAGUAUGUUUAUAUUCAAUAACAGUAUUGUAAUUCAUUGAGUUAACUAGUAAAUUGUGUGCUUUUGAAAAAACAUGAAAAAUGUAAAUUGACAGCAUACUUCAUUUGGAAAAAAGUAAAAGAUCCGAGGAACUAGUAUGUCACUUAUUUAUUUUUAUUUUAUUUUAUUUUUUACUUUUUGAGACAGGGUCUUGCUCUGUCACCCAGGCUGGAGUGCAGUGGCAUGGUCACAGCUCACUGCAGCCUUGACUUCCUGGGCUCAGGUGAUUCUCCCACCUCAGCCUUCCAAGUAGCUGGGACUACAGGCAUGCACCACAUUGCCUGGCUAAUUUUUUGUGGAGAUGGGGUUUCGCCAUGUUGUCCAGGCUGUUCUUGAACUCCUGGGCUCAGGCAAUUUGCCUGCCUCAUUCUCCCAAAGUGCUGGGAUUAUAGGCGUGAGCCACUGCGCCCAGCCUUACUUAUUUUUAAAUCAGAUUUUUUAAUCAACUAAAACAGCUAUGAGUUAAGUACCUGCCCUGCAAAAAUUUUUAGAAAAAGUUUUAGGAUUAUGAAAUUAAGAAUUAUUUUCCUUAACUGGAACAGUUCUAAAAUUUAUCUGAUACUUCUCUAACAAGUGAGUGAUCUCAUGUAACCCCAGUUUGUAUCUUAAAGGCUGCAGCAUAGAAUUGAGCUGUAUAACAGUGUUAGAACUGUCAAGUGAUAAUCACAGAACAGUUUGUAUCGGUUUUAUAAUUCUCAUGUCUUGAUCAGAUCUGAAGGAAAUAGGCAUACCCUCCAACAUUCUAAAAAUUAUUUAUUUUUAUUAGGAUUUGUUUAUUAAAGUUCCACGAGCUGCUUUAUGGUCAGUUGGGCUGAGUAGUAGAUAUCUUAAAGACAUGCAGUGAAAGUGAACCCUGUCAUAUCAUGGUGCCUCUUUCAAGGUUCCUCUGUAAGUUCCUCAUCUUGCAGAAUUAUUUCAAUACCAAGGUAUGGUUGAACCAGCUGUCCAGCCUUAACUCUAUUUAGUGCCCCAUUACUAAUGUUCUUUUAACUGGUUUGUAUGUGUUUUAACUGUCCAGUGUUUGGAUUUUACCUCUUGAUAGCUCCAUUUGUCCCUGGUGCUGCUUUUAAGGAUGUAGGGCCAUGUGAUCAGGUAUCAAGUUGAGUAGGUACGCAGUUGGCCUGGUGAUGUAUCUGUGCCUGUUUUAUCUUCUCCCAGGAAGAGCUGCUUUGGUAUAGUUGUUUACUUGGAUUCAUACAAAGAACAGGGCAGCAAUCUUGGAAAGCUUUCUGAAGCUUAUAAGAACCUGAAGGGGUUUGGAGGGGGAACAGUAACAAAGGCUGCCUUUAUGUCUUUGGUCACAAAGCACAUAGAUGUAUGUUCUGUAAAGACUAAAGUGAUUGUUAUACCAGGGCUUCCUGACCUUCGGGAGAGACUCAAAAAAGCAGAGAGGAGCACAAAGUGAAGUUAAUUUGGUUGGCUUGCUUUAUCUGGUUUCUCAUUUUCUUUCAAUUUAAACCUGAACAUAACACCCUUCUCCGAUACCUAUCCAGCAGACUCCUGGUUGGGAAGCCCUGUAUUAAAUUUUGAGAAUGUACACAGUUUUCUUUUGUACAGUGCUUUACAACUGCUAAAAGUUAACUUGUUUAAAGCAAAACAAGACCUUGAAAGGUCAAUCAUAUUAAAGCUGGUUUGAUUAUUAAUAGUUAUCUUUUAGGAAGAAGCUUUUUUCCCUAUGUAAGAUGUCAUACUGCAGAUUUAAAAUAUAGACUAUCAAUAAAAUGCAUGAAGUGAUCAUUUGUGCUUGAUCAUCUCUCCUUGGGUUUUUCUUUAAAAAGGGGAAUCUGCUAUAAAGGUUCUGUUGCUUCAAACCAAUGUCAAAUAGACUUGAUUUUUAGAGUCAUGGAAUUACAGUGCAACCUUGAUUUUUAUUCCCCUCACUGCUAUGAGUGUGGGCAGGUACUGGUUUAUAUGUUAUAACUUCCGUUUUAUCUGUGUUGUGUAGUUGAAUGGCUUAAUCGUUGAGUGGUAAAAUAAAAGAUUAUAUUCCAAUACAAGAAUCCUGGAAAGAUUUAUGUGAAUGACAUUUUAAGUAGGCGCAUCUUUGCUGUUUCUUGUAUUCUCGCCAUUGCUCUGACCACUCCCUUGCUUGCCCUGUAUAUAUACAAAAACUUGUAGGUGUGCACGUGUGCUUGUACUUCUGUCUUCCAUUUCUAUCUUAAUCUCUUAAACAUAUUGCUUAAGCCACUAAGAUGUCCUUGUUUCAAGUAAAUCGUCACAUUGUGACACCUGGUGUAUUGUAUUAUAGUUUCAUUUCCUCUGGUGCCUGCAGAGCUAUCUGUCAUUGGCAUCAUAACUCGGUUUCUCAGGAUAGUUUUGAUGUAGUCAGCUCUUCAACUCAUGACCUUCCCAAGGUUUUAAGUUUAGUGUCAUUCAUGAUUUUAUUAUUUGAAACUCAAUACCACCAUCAAAAAGUUAGUGCUCUAGACAAUGAAGCCAAAGCACAGGCAUCUUAGGUCAGUGAAAAGGAUCCAGACAUAAAUUAGCCAGGUGUGGUGGUACACAGCUGUGGUCCCAGCUACUUGGGAGGCUGAGGUGGUAGAAUCACUUGAGCCCGGGAGGUCAAGGCUGCAGUGAGCCAUGAUCAUGCUGAUGCACUCCAGCCUGGGUUACAGAGCAAAACCUUGUCUCAAAAAAACCCCCAGAUACCUAGAAGAAAGGAUUCGAUAAAUCUGGGUGGAUUAUAAACUGAACUCUUAAUGGUCAUUUUAAAAAAUAAGAAAGCAAGGGUCCAGUUUCUUUGAGGUCUUUGAAUUUAGACAAGAUUUAACUAUAAGGCCUUGCAUGGAUUACUAACUAUAAUUAAAUUAGCUAAACUUUUCUGGUUGCUGUCAGGCAUUGUAUUAAGUAUUCUAUAUAAAUUAUUUAAUCAUCACAGUGACUGUGAGGUGAAAGUAUACCACCCAUUUUAUAGGUAAUGCAGCUGAGAUACAGAUGUUUGGUAAUUUGCCCAGGUCACAUAGUAAGUAGCAGAUUAUUUGCAAUCAUCUUUGAUGCAGUCAUCUUCCUUGUGCUCUUAAUCCCACUACUAUAUGACUUCUAAUUUGUUUCUUAGUAUUUAUCCCAAGCCCUAGACUAGAUUGCUUAUGAGGUGUGAUUUCUUAGGAAAAACAUCAGUUUUGGCUGGUUUGCCAAGAAAAAAAAAGGCCAAAUUGGUUUUUGUUUAUUUUUUUGUUUGUUUGAGAUGGAUUCUCGCCCUGUCGCCCAGGCUGGAGUGCAAUGGUGCGAUCUUGGCUCACUGCAACCUCUGCCUCUGGGUUCAAACGAUUCUCCUGCCUCAGCCUCCCGAGUAGCUGGGAUUACAGGCGCCCGCCACCACGCCCAGCUAAUUUUUCUAUUUUUAGUAGAGACAGGGUUUCACCAUGUUGGCCAGGCUGGUCUUGAACCCCUGAUCCCAUGAUCUGCCCGUCUCGGCCUCCCACAGUGGUGGUAUUACAGGCGUGAGCCACCACGCCCGGCCGCAAAUUGUUUUUUGUUUUUUUGUUUUUUGGAGGAUUAAUGGUAAUAUACUGUAAAUUCAGUAAAGCACUGGGCAUUACCAGAUACACCUUAGCACUAUGAAUAACAUGAACUAUCAUUUUAGCAGUUUAAGUGUACCUUGUAAUCAGCCCUAGGGCAAACGGUAUCAAGGUGUUUUAUUUCCAGAAGUCUCAAAAUAGACUGGAAUAAAAAUUUGGUGAAUUCAUCAACACAGACAAUGGGUCCACGUCUUGCAGCUACAGCUGCUGCAGCUACUCCUGCUGUCCGCACCGUUCCACAGUAUAAAUAUGCUGCGGGAGUUUGCAAUCCUCAGCAACAUCUUAAUGCACAGCCACAAGUUACAGUGCAACAGCCUGCUAUUCAUGUACAAGGUCAGGAACCUUUGACUGUUUCCAUGUUGGCAUCUGCCCCUCAAGAGCAAAAGCAAAUGUUGGGUGAAUGGCUGUUUCCUCUUAUUCAAGCCAUGCACCCUACUCUUGCCGGUAAAAUCACUGGCGUGUUGUUGGAGAUUGAUAAUUCAGAACUUCUUCAUAUGCUCAAGUCUCCAGAGUCACUCCAUUCUAAGGUUGAUGAAGCUGUAGCUGUACUACAAGCCCACCAAGCUAAAGAGACUGCCCAGAAAGCAGUUAACAGUGCCACCGGUGUUCCAACUGUUUAAAAUUGAUCAGGGACCACGAAAAGAAACUUGUGCUUCACCAAAGAAAAAUAUCUAAACAUCGAAAAACUUAAAUAUGGAAAAAAAUAUCAAAAUAUAAAAGAAGGAAACUGAA